ACUAGGGCGACGGCCGGACGCCUCCGCGUUACGGGAUGAAUUAACGGCGGGUUCCGCACGGAGGUUGUGACCCCUACGGAGCCCCAGCUUGCCCACGCACCCCACUCGGCGUCGCGCGGCGUGCCCUGCUUGUCACAGGCUGAAAAACAGAGUGGGUACUCUCUUCUGGGAAGCUGGCAACAAAUGGAUGAUGUGAUAUAUGCAUUCCAGGGGAAGGGAAAUUGUGGUGCUUCUGAACCCAUGGUCAAUUAACGAGGCAGUUUCUAGCUACUGCACGUACUUCAUAAAGCAGGACUCUAAAAGCUUUGGAAUCAUGGUGUCAUGGAAAGGGAUUUACUUUAUACUGACUCUGUUUUGGGGAAGCUUUUUUGGAAGCAUUUUCAUGCUGAGUCCCUUUUUACCUUUGAUGUUUGUAAACCCAUCUUGGUAUCGCUGGAUCAACAACCGCCUUGUGGCAACAUGGCUCACCCUACCUGUGGCAUUAUUGGAGACCAUGUUUGGUGUAAAAGUGAUUAUAACUGGGGAUGCAUUUGUUCCUGGAGAAAGAAGUGUCAUUAUCAUGAACCAUCGGACAAGAAUGGACUGGAUGUUCCUGUGGAAUUGCCUGAUGCGAUAUAGCUACCUCAGAUUGGAGAAAAUUUGCCUCAAAGCGAGUCUCAAAGGUGUUCCUGGAUUUGGUUGGGCCAUGCAGGCUGCUGCCUAUAUCUUCAUUCAUAGGAAAUGGAAGGAUGACAAGAGCCAUUUCGAAGACAUGAUUGAUUACUUUUGUGAUAUUCACGAACCACUUCAACUCCUCAUAUUCCCAGAAGGGACUGAUCUCACAGAAAACAGCAAGUCUCGAAGUAAUGCAUUUGCUGAAAAAAAUGGACUUCAGAAAUAUGAAUAUGUUUUACAUCCAAGAACUACAGGCUUUACUUUUGUGGUAGACCGUCUAAGAGAAGGCAGGAGGCAGAGCGAGGGAAGUAAAGGACCACUUCAAGGAGAACUACAAAUCACUGCUCAAGGAAAUCAGAGAGGACACAAACAAAUGGAAAAACACUCCAUGCUCAUGGAUUGGAAGAAUCAAUAUCGUGAAAUUGGCCAUACUGCCCAAAGCAAUUUACAGAUUCAAUGCUAUUCCCAUUAAACUGCCGUUGACAUUCUUCAUAGAAUUAGAAAAAACUCUUAAAAUUCAUAUGGAACCAACAAAAAGCCCAUAUAGCCAAGACAAUCUUAAGCAAAAAGAACACAGCUGGAGGCAUCACAUUACCUGACUUCAAACUAUACUACAGGGCUACAGUAACCAAAAUAGCAUGGUACUGUUACAAAAACAGACACAUAGACCAAUGGAACAGAAUAGAGAACUCAGAAAUAAGUCCGUGCAACUACAGCCAUCUGAUCUUUGACAAACCUGACAAAAACAAGCAAUGGGGAAAGGAUUCCCUAUUUAAUAAAUGGUGCUGGGAGAACUGGCUAGCCAUAUGCAGAAAACUGAAACUGGACCCCUUCCUUACACCUUAUGCAAAAAUUAACUCAAGAUGGAUUAAAGACUUAAAUGAAAAACCCAAAACUAUAAAAACCCUAGAAAAAAAUCUAGGCAAUACCAUUCAGGACAUAAGCAUGGGCAAAGAUUUCAUGAUGAAGAUGACAAAAGCAAUUGCAACCAAAGCAAAAAUUGACAAAUGGGAUCUGAUUAAACUAAAGGGCUUCUGCACAGGAAAAGAAACUAUCAUCAGAGCAAACAGACAUUCUACAGAAAGGGAGAAAAUUUUUGCAAUCUAUCCAUCUGACAAAGGUCUAAUAUUCAGAGUCAACAAGAAACUAAAACAAAUUUACAAGAAAAAACAACCCCAUUAAAAAAGUGGGCAAGGGACAUGAACAGACACUUCUCAAAAGAAGACAUUUAUAUGGCUAAUAAACUUAUGAAAAAAAGCUCAACAUCACUGAUCAUCAGAGAAAUGCAAAUCAAAACCACAAUGAGAUACCAUCUCACACCAGUCCAAAUGGCAAUUAUUUAAAAGUCAUGAAACAACAGAUGCUGGCAAGGCUGUGGAGCGAGAGGAAUGCUUUUACAUUGUUGGUGGGAAUGUAUAUUAGUUCAACCAUUGUGUAGCUGGGACUACAGGCGUCCACUACCACGCCCGGCUAAUUUUUUUGUAUUUUUAGUAGAGACAGGGUUUCACCAUGUUAGCCAGGAUGGUCUCGAUCUCCUGACCUCAUGAUCCACCCGCCUCAGCUUCCCAAAGUGCUGGGAUUACAGGCAUGAGCCACCGCGCCCAGCCAAGGAAAUAUCUUUAUAGAUGUCUUCUUGUGUACCUGUGUAAGAAUUCCUUUGGGAUAUACAGUCAUGCAACACAUAAUGACGUUCUAGUUAGUGGCAAACCACAUAUAUGAUGGCAGUCUCAUAAGAUCAUAAUGGAGCUAGAAAAUUCCUAUCACCUGGUGACAUCAUCACAUGUUUGUGAUGAUGCUGAUGUAAACCACUAUGCUACCAGUUGUGUAAAACAGUAGCACAUAAAAUUAUAUACCGUAAUGAUAAUGACUAUGUUACUGAUUUACAUAGUUACUGUACUAUACUUUUUAUUGUUACUUGAGUGUAUUCCUUCUGCUUAUAGUAAAAGCAGUAAAACAGCCCCAGGCAGGUCCUUCAGGAGGUAUUCCAGAAGAAGGCAUUGCUGUCAUAGGACAUGACAGCUCCAUGCUUGUUAUUACCUCUGAAGACCUUGCAGUGAGACAAGAUGUGGAGGUGAAGACAGUGAUAUUGAUGAUCCUGACCCUGUGUAGGCCUAGGCUGUGUGUGUGUGUGUGUGUGUGUGUGUGUGUGUGUGUGUGUGUGUGUGUGUGUGUCUUAAUUUUUAACAGUUUUUUUUAAAAAAGUUUUUAUAAUUAAAGGUUAUGGAAUCAGGAUAGAAAGAAAGUCUUUUUGUACAACUUUACAAUAGGUUUGUGUUUUAAGCGAAGUGUUAUAAAAGAGUCAAGUUUUAAACAUUUAGAAGUUUACUCACACCUGUAAUCCCAGCACUUUGGGAACCCGAGGCAGGUGGAUCACCUGAGGUCGGGAGUUCAAGACUAGCCUGGCCAACAAGUUGAAACCUUGUCUCUUCUAAAAAUACAAAUAUUAGCUGGGCGUGGUGGCAGGUGCCUCUAUUCCCAUCUACUUGGGAGGCUGAGGCAGGAGAAUAGCUUGAACCUGGGAGGCGGAUGUUGCUUGCACUCCAGCCUGGGUGACAGAGUGAGACUCCAUCUCAAAAAAAAAAAAAAAUUUAUAAGUUUAGAGUAAAAAAGUUACAGUAAGCUAAGGUUAAUUUAUUAUUGAUGAAAGUUUUUUAAUAAAUUUAGUGUAGCCUAAGUGUACAGUGUUUAUUAAAGUCUACAGUAGUGUACAGUGGUGUCCUAGGCCUUCACAUUCACUCACCCUCACUCACUGACUCACCCAGAGCAACUUCCAGUCCUGCAGACUCCAUUCAUGGUAAGUGCCCUGUAGAGGUAUACUAUUUUUUAUCUUUUAUACUGUAUUUUUACCAUACCUUUUCUAUGUUUAGACACACAAAUACUUAGCAUUAUGUUACAAUUGCCAACAAUAUUCAGUACAGUAACAUGCUGUACAGGUUUGUAGCCUAGGAGCAACAGGCCAUACCAUAUAGCCUAGGUGGGUCAUAGACUAUAUACUGUCUAGGUUUGUGUGAGUAUGCUCUAUGAUGUUCCCAUGACAAAAAAAUUGCCUAAAGACACAUCUCUCAGAACAUAUCCCCGUCAAGUGACACAUAGUUGUAUGUCCAAGAGUAGAACUGCUGAGUCAUAGGGUUUGGUAACCUUAAUUUGACCAGCCCCAAAUUAUACUACAUAAUAGAUACUCCCCUCUAAACACCCACUGGCAAUGCACAAGGGUGCCUGUUUCCUCUCAUUCCUGUGAACACUUGGUAUUAUCCAGCUUUCUACUCUUUGCCAGUCAAAUAGGUAUAUUUUAAUUUGGUUUUGUCUGAUUACAAAGGAUUUUCACAUGCCUGAUAUUUUCUGGGUUUCCUCAUCUAUUCAUUGCCUGUUUAUAUCUUGUCUGUGUUUCUAUUGGGAUUACUAUAGUGACUUGUUAAUUCGCACUAGUUCUUAUGUUCUAGAUAUAAUCCCUUGUUGAAUUUUAGACAUUGCAGGUAUGUUCUAUUUUAUUACAUAUUCAUUGAACAGAAAUUCCUGGUGUAAUCAAAUUAAGAAGUUUUUAUCUUACGACCUAUGCUCUUGAAGUCUGGUUUUUAAAAACCUUUCUUGUUACUUGGUCUCCAUUUUCUUUUGUUAAUUGUAUAAUUAUGUUUUACAUUUCAGCUUUAUCCAUCUGGAGUCCCUUACAUGUGUUGUUUGGUGUGAGGAUCUGGUUUUAUUUUUCUCCAACAGUGUGUACUUAAUCUGUUAUUCUCCAUUGAUUUGUGAUGUUACCUUUAUCAUAUAUUAAGUCCCCAUAUAUUCAUGAGAAUGGCUUUGAACUCUAUUCUGAUACUUGUUUUUCCACAACCACUUGAUUCUUUUAGAAUGUAUUUUCCAUAGUGAAGACCCAGUUUCUUCUAAAUCUCAAGGAACUAGUUUAUGCAUGUGUUAUACCAGGAUAGCCUUUUUGUGUGCAUAACUGUUUAGGCAUUUCAGCCCACAGUGAUCCUGUCCUCCUUUGAACUCAUAGUGUUCAUUCUCUACUACACUCACCUCACUUCUCUUAAAAUUUUCUAUUAACUUGUAUUCGUUUCCUGUGUUAUUACUUAACUUUUCACAUAUUUAUAUGUUGUACUUCAACUAGAUUAUAAACUUCUAAAAGGCAAGGAUUGCUUCCAUGUCUUUAAAUCUCCCAUGGUAGCUGUAGCUAGCACAGGACUUAAAAUCAUUAUCAUAAGCAUGAUUUAGUGAGCAAUUAUUAAACUCUUUAUUGAUACUUUUGAUGUGAUGAAUGCAUGUCUUAACAUAAUUUUAAGCACAUAAAGGCAAUGACCGAUUUUUGAAGGAUAUAGGACAAAUAUGCAGUUUCUACAUGUACAAAUUGAACAUAGCCAUACCCCCUGCAUUUUUCUAAUAACUAGACUUUGUCACAUAUUACUUCCUCUAUUUCUUAAAAGGUUUUAGUUUACUAAUUUUUUCGUUCCUUCUUUAGUAAUUGCAUUUUUUUUUUUAGGUUUCCUUAAUAAACCCUGUGAAAAGCAAUGUGCUAAAUAAAUUAUAUGCAGGGCAAAGCAAUACAUUAUAAUUAGGCAUUCCAUUAUUGAAUUGAUGCCUCUGGCUUCUCAUGGUCUCUGUCUAAUCCUGAAACAAAUUCUUUUUGUGGACAAAUAUUAGCCUAUAAUAAUUAUUCAUCUAAGCUAACGCUUUUCAUUAAAUCUCCUUCUGAUUAAGAUAGCUCCAUAAGUACAGACUGAUUUAAUUUAACAUGAUUUAUCCACUUGUGUAUCAAGGUCUGGUGGAAAUUGUUUUUAACACCAGAGGAUUGUGAAUAUUAAGAUCAUCUUUAUAUUAACAGAUCUCUCAGGUAUUUAAGACCUUGUUGUUUGAAUAGUUAUAUAAGCCUAGGUCUGAUGUCACUCUGCUAAAUUCAAGAGUAUCACAAGUGCUGUAACAGGCUGUCAUUAAAAACAAUAUGGAUUCUGUUUUAUAUUAUAAUGUUGGAGCUUAGAGUUAGUACAUUCUUGUGUUACUUGGGUUUGGGAAUCAAUUUUCAUUCCAGCUGGUUGGUCCAACACAUUUAAUGUCUUUUCUGUUUUACCAGAAGUUCAGUGUUAUUAAAAACAAGUAAAUCAUAGAUAUAUAUUCUGAAUUAAGGGUCUCCACGGACAUGAAUAUAACUUUUUAAAAAAUUUCUUGGACUUAACUGUUAUUAUUUCCUCACCUGUUACCAUCCUUGUGCUUUUCUUCAGUUUUUUUAAUGCUGGCUAUGUAAUAGAUACCAAACACUGAGUUUAAUUUUGUUUUUUUUUCACUUCUUCCUUGAUCAUCUUUCCCCCAAUAUUCCUCCCUUAAUUUGUUAAAUUCUGGCUUCACCACUGCUCUUCUACUUUUAGCUUUUUUUUUUUUUUCCUAUCAGUAGUCAACAGACUCAUUAGCAUUUUUCUUCUGGCCUUUUUGUCCAUUUUUUUUCUUUUUGGUCCUUUUAUAGUCUUUCCUGCUUCAUUAUAUAUGCAUGAGAAAGUUUGCAUUGCUCUAUGUGAACAUGAUAAAGCUACAUGAAUUAAUUCUAUGAAACCAAAGCAUAUAUUCUAAUUUGCUGCAACCAAAAAUUCUUGAAAAUAAACUAUAUAAUGUCCUAAUUAUAAUUUAGCUCCAGUUUUAGGAAAUCCCAGAGAACAGAGAGUGUGUGUGUAUACACUCACACUUUCAGUUGAGGGUGAAAGAGAGUGCCAUGAAAGCAAAAGGAAAGGCAUUCUAGCAUGUGGAACUUUCUGAGGUCCCAUUUCCAGCCGUAUCCUCUUUAUUUUCAGGUUUCUAAGAGUUGUUAACUGUUCUUUCUCUCUCCCCCUGACUCUGCUCUGCCCCAUGUGUGCUGUUCUCAGAAGACAGUGGUGUGUAUGGUAGGACCCUGAGUCAGUAGGCUGAAGACUUACAGAAAGAAGGUACCUUGGAGUCAGGACUGGAAGCUGAGGGAUAACAGGCCAAGUCAGGCUGAGAUUCUUAACUGGUCUGGGCUCUGGGCAUAGCAGCAAAGAAGAGCUUACUUCAUCUGGGUCAGCUGAGGGAAGUGGUUCAUGAACCGCUUAGCAGACCACUUGAACUAAUAGGAGGAGGAUGACGCAGAACUCAAGUGAAGUACUGUGGUCAUUUGCAGAAGAGUUUCUCCUGGGAGGAGGUCAGAGUAGAAAUGGGCGUAUCAUGCCCAUAAGGCAGCAAUUACUGUUUUCAGAGCCGUGUCUGCACUGAUGGAAAUGCCAGCUCUGUGAAAUUUUUUUCAAGCUGGUGGGACUCCCAUGUGUCCUGUGGAUAGAAAGAAAAAAAAUAGCACAGUAGAAAAUGAAGCUUUCUUUUCUGUGAGGAAAAGACUUUCUGUGAGGAGGUUGGUGGUUCUAUUUAAAGACACAGUCUUGAGAGUUGAUUAGGAAACAAGUACUUCUACAGUAAUACCUUAAUUAAUGAAGAGGCUAUAUUCGGGAAUGUUUAAUGAAGUUUCUGUUGUUAUCAGAGAGAAAAUGAAGCAAGCACAGGGGAUUGCAUUCCAGAAUGUCAGGAAAGAAUUUCAGUUUAAAAACAACACUGUAUGUUUAACAUCGUCAAAUAUGCCAUAACUAAAGAGUAUUUAUAUCACGGUUUGAAGGGAGAGGGAGAGAGGAGCAUAUCAAACUAACAUAAGCUCCUUAAACCUAUAAAAGGCACCUAUCAUCAUUGAAGAGGUCUCUAGCUUCCUGUCCUUGUGGCGCCCUGUGCCUAUUCAGAUGUUGGUCAUUUAGUGCUGUUGACCUACUGUUAACACCACAUACAUGUGACCUUGACUUCCCAGUAUAUCCUCUGAAACAUUAUUAUCUCAGCUUGCCUGACAACUCAUGAAGAACCCCAGUGCUUUAACAAUAAUAUAGUGAUUGCACAGAUUGCAAGUAGCAGAACUACAGAGUAUCUAAGGCUUGGCAAAGAAUGUCUCAUGUCCAGAACAGAAGCACAAAUUCCUGUCUGCCUUCUCUGCUAUGGUCUGAGGGAUCAUUAAUCACAAUUACUUUCCAGCGACAGUCUCUCAUAAUGCACCUUUCUACUGCAGGCUGUUAGGGAAGGCUCUAUUCUUAGGCUCUCUGCCAAGAAGUACCCCAGAGACAGAAGCUCAGCUCAGUUUCCCCUUUUCUGCUUAUUCAAUUUAUAUAUUUCCUGAGCUCACUGAAGCAGCACAGGAAUACACCAAUGAAUAAAAUAAACAAAAAUUUAGACAAUAAGUACGUAAAAUUUAUAGUAUGUCAGAUGAUGGGGCUUACAGAGAAAAUAAAUCAAGGAAGAGGGAAGACUGAAGUAGGGUAGUCAGGGCUCCCCUGAAAAGAGGAAUUUGGGGGAAGAGGAUCCCUAGUAGAAGGAACAAUAACGUGCCUGAGAUGAGAAUGUGCCUAGUGUGUUCAAAGAAGAACAAGAGAUGCAGUGUGGCUAGACCAGAUCAAGUCACAUGAGCAGUAGCAGAGAAUGAGGGCAGAAAGGUAAAUGUUUGCCAGAUAGGCCACCAUGGGAGUUUGGUGUUCUCUCUGAGAUGGGCAGCCACUGGGGAGAAGGGGUGAAGGGGGAGGGGUUAUAAGAUUGUGACUGACAUUAUUAAAGGAUUACUCUGGCUGUAAUGUUAAGAAAAAUCUGUAGGUCGGGCAGGUGGGCAAACAGAGAAACCAAUUAGAAAGUUAUUUGUAAUAAUGCAGGAAAGAGAAGUGGAGAGUGAGGUAAAAUUAGUGAGGUUGCAAAAAAUGGCUGGAUUCUAGAUACAUUUUAAGGUGGAAGUGUAGGGGUGGGUUGCCCCUACACACCUGUGGGUGUUUCUCGUAAGGUGGGACGAGAGAUUUGGAAAAGAAAAAGACACAGAGACAAAGUAUAGAGAAAGAAAUAAGGGGAACCGGGGAACCAGCGUUCAGCAUAUGGAGGAUCCCGCCAGCCUCUGAGUUCCCCUAGUAUUUAUUCAUCAUCUGUGGGUGUUUCUCGAAGAGGGGGAUGUGUCAGGGUCACAAGACAAUUGUGGGGAGAGGGUCAGCAGACAAACAUGUGAACAAAGGUCUUUGCAUCAUAGACAAUGUAAAGGAUUAAGUGCUGUGCUUUUAGAUAUGCAUACACAUAAACAUCUCAAUGCUUUACAAAGCAGUAUUGCUGCCCACAGGUCCCACCUCCAGCCCUAAGGCGGUUUUUCCCUAUCUCAGUAGAUGGAGCAUACAAUCGGGUUUUAUACCGAGACAUUCCAUUGCCCAGGGACGGGCAGGAGACAGAUGCCUUCCUCUUGUCUCAACUGCAAGAGGCAUUCCUUCCUCUUUUACUAAUCCUCCUCAGCACAGACCCUUUACGGGUGUCGGGCUGGGGGACGGUCAGGUCUUUCCCUUCCCACGAGGCCAUAUUUCAGACUAUCACAUGGGGAGAAACCUUGGACAAUACCUGGCUUUCCUAGGCAGAGGUCCCUGCGGCCUUCCGCAGUUUUUGUGUCCCUGGGUACUUGAGAUUAGGGAGUGGUGAUGACUCUUAAGGAGCAUGCUGCCUUCAAGCAUCUGUUUAACAAAGCACAUCUUGCACCGCCCUUAAUCCAUUUAACUCUGAGUUGACACAGCACACGUUUCAGAGAGCACGGGGUUGGGGGUAAGGUUAUAGAUUAACAGAAUCUCAAGGCAGAAGAAUUUUUCUUAGUACAUAACAAAAUGGAGUCUCCUAUGUCUACUUCUUUCUACACAGACACAGUAACAAUCUGAUCUCUCUUGCUUUUCCCCACAUGGAAGCAAUAGGAUUUUUUGAUGGGUCGGGUGUGGAGUAUAAGAAAAUGAGAGGGAACUAGUGUGACUGCAAGGUUCUUGGCCUCAACUGAAGGAAAGGCAGUUUUGCCUUUUAACUGCAACAAAGACUGUGGUAAGUACAGGUUUUGGGGGAAAGGCCAAAAAGCAGUUCCAUUUAAGCCAUGUUAAGUUUGAGCUACUUAUUAGAUAUCCAUAGGGAGUUAUGAAAUUAGUAAAUAUGUGAGUCUAGAAAGGAGAGAGGCAGGAGAUACACAUUUGGUAGGCAUGACCACAUAUGAUAUUUAAAGCUGCAAGACUGAAAGAGAUCACCUAAGGAAUGAGUGUGGAUGGAGAAGAGUAAGAUCCCAGCCUAGUUAAUAGUAGGCAGUACAAUAUUAGGGAUCGGAGAACCAGGCCAUCCACAAAGAAGACUUCAGAGUGGCCUGUGAAGUUGGGGAAAAGCCAAGAGAGUAAGGUGACCAGGAAGCCAAGAGGGAGGGAGGCAUUGGAUUUGGUACAUAAAGGUCACCGAGGACAGUUCUGGUGGAAUGAUGAGGGCAGAAGCUUCAUUGGCAUGGGUUCGAGAGAGAAAUGAAAGAGGAUUGAAGACAGUGAGUAUAGACAGCUCAGGAAGUUUAGCUGUGUAAGUGAACACAGAGAUGAGUGGUCACUAGAAGGAGAGGUGAGCCAAGAGGGAAUGAUGGGAGAAGUUAUAAUAUGUUGAUGGUCAAGAUAGAAUGACUGAUUAAAGGGGAAUUGCUGGGGCUCUGUUCCUGAGUAGGCAAGAGCAGGUGAGAUAGAAGACAUAGGUGGAGGGAUUGGCCCUAAAUACAUGCGUGGACAGAUCCUCCUUAUGAAAAAAAGAAGGCAAAGUGUAUGAACUCACACAGUAGUAGGAGAGUAUAUAGGGUGGUACGAGUUGUGCAAAUUUCUUUUGAUUGAUUUUCUCAGUGAAAUAGGAUGAGAAUGAAGGAUAGUGAGGAAGUUAUUGGAAGUUUUUGAGAAAAGCAAAGUCAUGAAGUCCUCAAAUCCAAGCAACUGGGACACAGAAUGGACUAAGGAAAUAUGUAUGUUGAGCAGUACUAAGGAGCUGCUUUUGGCCAGUGAUCAGGAAUUUACCAAGGACUCCCACUAGCCUUCAUUCCCUGCCGAAAAACUUAAAUACUUCCACCAAAACUUGUGCCUAAUAGGCUCAAAUAAGUUUCUGGGAGAAAAGAGACACCACAUAUCAAAAAGUCUUUCUCCAUAAGACUUAUGUAAAUGUGUAAAGUGAAAGGAAAUAAAGCCUUAGGAACUGGGCAUUCAAAUCUAGUUUGGCUUAUGCACUUUGAGUCUGUGGUAAGGAAUUUAUCUGGGAAAGGUACAUUAUAUACUGCAAAAAACACAUCAAGAGUACUAAAUCAGAUUACUUGCCGGUUACGUCUUCAGACUGAUUGAAUGAUCAAGACUUAUGACAUCUAUUCACAUUGGAGUAUAAUCAGUGAAUUGAUCAGCUUGUGUAAGGGAUUGAAAUGAGACCCUUCCCUACCUUGGAAAUGGGUAGAGGGCACUAGACAGAGGGAGAGUUGUGGUCUCCACUGAGUUAGUCUUCACAGUUUACCCAGGCCAGUUUCAUCUAUAAGAACUGUGCAUGUGUAAUUAGAAGCUACUCAAAGGUGAUUUUGACACAAGCUGUCACACCAUGUGCACAGCUGAUAGGGAAUGUUGCUGUUGAAUUGCAAUGGUAAGUGAACGGUUUUUUUGUUGUUGUAUUUUGGUUGCUGGUGGAGGGAGUACUUAGCAGGAGAAAGUUGAAAUGGAUGUUUAAACCAGUUUCCAAAUGUGUUGAGUUUCUGAAUCAUAGUAUUGAUUAAAAGCAAAAAUACAUCCUUCAAAUCUGAAUCAAACAGAUUAGAUGCCAUACUGUCAUUGUAAUAUUUGCUCUGAGUUUUACAGGAGGAAUUGAAGGGUGCAAGAGUGUGUGUAUGUGUUUGUUUUGUUUGAUACACCUAAGCCCUGCUACUACUGUAGUAAUCUAAUAAAUUAGAGCUAUAUGCUUCUAAAAUAUUGAUUGCAAGACACAUUGUCACUUUUCUUCUAAUAUUUUUAUUGUUUUCUCUGUGAAUUCUAAUUGAACUAUUUGUAACUGCUUCAGAAAUAUGUUGAUGUAACCUUUUUCCUUUCUAGAUAGUAGCAAGAAAACAUGGUAGUUAUUAUUUGUGACCCUGAAGGAAAUUAACGUCCUAGAAAUUUUUAAAUGUCAGCUUGCACUUAAAGUGAUCCCUUAAUUAGGGAAUUAUAUCUUGCAUUAACCAGGAAAGGAAAAAGGAUGCAAAAUAACAAUGAAAAGCUUGUCGGAUAUGUUAAUGCUUAUUUGAAUGAAUAGGAAAAGAUCCUGUUUCAAAUAAAAUGCUAAUACCAAAAAAAAAAAAUUGAAAUCAUACAUGUGAAUAAAUUUGUUUCAAACUCUAAAUAAUGUUUUCUAACAUUUUGGUUUGACAAGAAUCCACGCAGCCUUUUAGAAAGCUCUGUUUAGACUAUAGCACAUAUUACAGAUUUGUGAUAUCACUUAAAUUUUUUUAGGGGAAAUAUUUGAGACGCCUUAAAAAAACAGCUUUUAGAGGUAGAAUUUACUUGCUGUAAAAUGUACUCAUUUUAAGUGUACAGUUAGAUGUGUUUUAUUAAAUGUAUAGAGCCACAUAUCUACCCACAGUCAAAAUAUGAAACAUGUCCAUCACCCCCAAAGGUUUUCUAUGUACCUCUGCAGUCAGGCCCCUUCCCUGAACGUUGGUCCCUGGAACCCACUGAUGUGCUUUCUGUCACCAUAGUUUUGCCUUUUCUAGAUUUUCAUAUAAAUGGAAUUAUAUAGUAUGUGGUCAUCUGUGUCUGGUUUAAGUUAGAAUAAUGCUGUUAAGUUUCAUCCAUAUUGCUGCAUGAAUCUGUAGUUUAUUCCUUUUUAUUGCUGAUUGGUAUUGCAUUGUGUGGAAUAUGCCACAAUUUCUUUAACCAUUCAUGGACUGAUAGACACCUGCGUUAUUUACAAUUUUAGGAUACUAUGUAUAAAAUUGCUACAGACAUUUUUGUAUUAAUACAAGAAUUUGUAUGGGCAUAUAUUUUCUUGGGCACAUACCUAUGCUGUCAUUCUCUGGUUUUCCAGAGUGUGUAGACUGUUUUACAUGUCCAUUAGUAUUAUUUGAGGGUUCCAGUUGUUCACCAUCCUGACCAAAACCUGAUAUUGUUAGCCUUUUUAACCUAGCCAUUCUAGUAAAUGUAUAUUAGAAUCUUAUUGUGGUUUUGGUUUAUGUUUCCCUAAUAGUAACUAAAGUGUUAAUUUAAGCAUCUUUUCCUGGGCUUAUUUGUCUUUCAUAUACCUUCACUGGUGAUAUGUUAAUUCCAAUUUUUUAUCCAAUUUAAAACAUUGGGUUGCUUUAUUAUGGGCUUGCAAGAAUGUUUUAUAUAUCUUAGAUACAAGUUAUUUAUAAUAUAUUUGGUUUGCAAACAUUAUCUUCCAAUCUGUGGCUUGCAUUUUUAUUUCCUUAAUACUGUCUUAUGAAGAGUAGAUGUGUUUAAUUUUGACAAAGUACAGUUUUUCAGUUUAUGAUUUGUGCUCUUCAAUGUCCUAUGUAAGAAACUGUUGCCUAGUCCAGGUCACAAAGAUUUUCUGUGUUCAUCUGUUUCUAGACUCUGUUCUGUUUCAUUGAUCUGUAUGUCUAACUCUCCUCCAGUACAAUAUUGUCUCGAUUACUGAACCUUUAUAGUAAGUCCUGAAAUGAGCAGCUAAUGCCAAGCCUCCAUCUUUUUCUUUUUCAAAAUUGUUUUCUUAUUCUAGUUCCUUUGCACAUCUAUAUAAAACUUAGAAUCAGUUUGUUAAUUUAUACACAGAAGCAGACUAGUUUUUAUUAGGAUUACUUUGAAUCUGUAGAGCAUUUUAGAGAAAUGUAAUCUUAAUAAUAUUGAAUUUUCCAGUCUAUGAACAUAGUAUAUCUCCCAUUUAUAUGGGUCUUUCUCUCAGUCAUGUUUUAUAGUUUGCAUUCUUGCACAUAUUUUAUAAAAUUUACAAGUGUUUCAUAACUUUGAUAUUGUAAAUGGUGUUUUUAAAAUUUCAGUGUUCCAAAGAAGGAAACAGCAGACACUGCGGUCUACUUGACAAGGGAGGGUGGGAGGAGGGAGAAGAGAUAACUAUUGGGUACUGGACUUAAUAACUGGGUGAUGAAAUAAUAUGUACAACAAACCCUCAUGACGUAUGUUUACCUAUGUAACAAACCUUCACAUGUAUACCCAAAGCUAAAAGUUAAAAAAAAUAAAAUUUCAGUGUUCAGUUAUUCAUUACUAGUAUCCAGAAAUAGAUUUAAUAAUGAACUUGUAUCCUGUAACCUUGCUAAAUCUACUUACCAGUUCUAGUAGUUUUGUAGACCCCUAAGGAUUCUCUACAUCAUAGUUUGUGAAUAAAGAGUUUUACUUUUCCUUUUUAA